CUUCUCUGACCUACUGAGCCUGGGAGUGAAUAUUCUGAGUCUCAACACCGUGUUCAGGCGUCCUCUUUCCAAGAGCUCCUCAUUCGCAACCCCGGGACACCUUCGGGAAGCUCCGGGGAAUGUCGGCGUGAGCACUGCUGGACGCCGGCAGAAUCGCGUCCUCCGGCACUUGCUGCGGCAUGCAUUCCUUGCGUGGCUCCUGGCCGCCGAGGAGAGAGGGAGGCUCGAACCUUCUUGGGCUAGGUCUAGGCCAUUUAUCUCCGCUCUCUCUUUCCCCAUCUGAGCCAUCUAAGAAGAGAAGUGACCUGGGGGGGUCGGAGGAUGGCUAGGCUGUGUGUGGGACCGGGUUUGGCCACUCGGGCCAAUUCAAGGUACAGCGAGCAGGCAGACCAGGGAGAGCUGCUGUCGCUGGGAAGAAGGUGCUAGCCCCAGCUGCUAAGGCGACGGGGGCGCGCCCCGUCUCUGAACCUCUGACCUGUGAAGGGGUCAUUUCAAGCAAAAGCUGGAAGGCUAGGGGCAAGAAGCCUAGGGGCAGGCGUCUGCGGAGAGAGCAGGGAGACGGGGAGGAAACCCUGGUGGGAAUUAAGCCGCCGCUCCAGGUAGGGGUCAUUUCUCCCAAAGCUUCCUUUCAAGGGUGUCAGGGAUGUCUGUGAGUGUGUGUGUGCAACUGAAAAAGAUCCUAGGUUUGCCGGACUGUGGGGCUCAUUGACUCUGGGUCUGCCCCUUCUGGUGUUCGAGUGUGCCUAGAGGUGGCAAGGAAGUGCGGUGGGGAGAGUCCUAGUUGAGUGCCCCUUUUAAAGUCUUUCCCCAGCCCUCAGCGCUUCCGCUUUUCUUGCUUCGCUCCUUGAUGCCCCAAUUGGGCAGGCACGCUGGUUAUGGGCACUUUGCAGAAGUUUAUAGCCAAUUACAACUGUAUAAAUCAAAGCGCCCUUUGGGGGCUGUCUCUGGGCAUCGGUUUCUGCGUCACUGUGCACAUGCUAGGGAGAGUCCUGGUGGGAAUGCCGCCGACCGGGGAGAAGGCCACAGAUCAGCCUCGGCCCUCACUUCUCCUUCCUCCACAGUGAAAACCAGGACGAAAGACAAAUAUCGAGUGGUGUACACGGACCACCAGCGGCUGGAGCUGGAGAAGGAGUUUCACUACAGUCGCUACAUCACCAUCCGGAGGAAAGCCGAGCUAGCCGCCACGCUGGGGCUCUCUGAGAGGCAGGUUAAAAUCUGGUUUCAGAACCGCAGAGCAAAGGAGAGGAAAAUCAACAAGAAGAAGUUGCAGCAGCAACAGCAGCAGCAGCCACCACAGCCGCCUCCGCCGCCACCACAGCCUCCCCAGCCUCAGCCAGGUCCUCUGAGAAGUGUCCCAGAGCCCUUGAGUCCGGUGUCUUCCCUGCAAGCCUCAGUGCCUGGCUCUGUCCCUGGGGUUCUGGGGCCAACUGGGGGGGUGCUAAACCCCACCGUCACCCAGUGACCCACCGGGUUCUGCAGCGGCAGAGCAAUUCCAGGCUGAGCCAUGAGGAGCGUGGACUCUGCUAGACUCCUCAGGAGAGACCCCUCCCCUCCCACCCACAGCCAUAGACCUACAGACCUGGCUCUCAGAGGAAAAAUGGGAGCCAGGAGUAAGACAAGUGGGAUUUGGGGCCUCAAGAAAUAUACUCUCCCAGAUUUUUACUUUUUCCCAUCUGGCUUUUUCUGCCACUGAGGAGACAGAAAGCCUCCGCUGGGCUUCAUUCCGGACUGGCAGAAGCAUUGCCUGGACUGACCACACCAACCAGGCCUUCAUCCUCCUCCCCAGCUCUUCUCUUCCUAGAUCUGCAGGCUGCACCUCUGGCUAGAGCCGAGGGGAGAGAGGGACUCAAGGGAAAGGCAAGCUUGAGGCCAAGAUGGCUGCUGCCUGCUCAUGGCCCUCGGAGGUCCAGCUGGGCCUCCUGCCUCCGGGCAGGCAAGGUUUACACUGCGGAAGCCAAAGGCAGCUAAGAUAGAAAGCUGGACUGACCAAAGACUGCAGAACCCCCAGGUGGCCUGCGUCUUUUUUCUCUUCCCUUCCCAGACCAGGAAAGGCUUGGCUGGUGUAUGCACAGGGUGUGGUAUGAGGGGGUGGUUAUUGGACUCCAGGCCUGACCAGGGGGCCCGAACAGGGACUUGUUUAGAGAGCCUGUCACCAGAGCUUCUCUGGGCUGAAUGUAUGUCAGUGCUAUAAAUGCCAGAGCCAACCUGGACUUCCUGUCAUUUUCACAAUCUUGGGGCUGAUGAAGAAGGGGGUGGGGGGAGUUUGUGUUGUUGUUGCUGCUGUUUGGGUUGUUGGUCUGUGUAACAUCCAAGCCAGAGUUUUUAAAGCCUUCUGGAUCCAUGGGGGGAGAAGUGAUAUGGUGAAGGGAAGUGGGGAGUAUUUGAACACAGUUGAAUUUUUUCUAAAAAGAAAAAGAGAUAAAUGAGCUUUCCAGAUUUCAGAUUCUGUAUUUAUCUUCAGAUUUUGUCUGCAACUAUUUUUUAUUUUUUAAAGAAAUGAAAUAUCUUCUCUGCUUGCAAGCUGAUUUGGAAAAUUCAGAGAGGGAGUGGAGAUUAUCUGGACAGCCUCAUUUUACCCCAGAGCAUCAGAAGCCUGAAAGAGCAGGUUCUGAGACCUUCCCUGCCCCCAAGCCUGAGCCCAGCCUUGGAAUGCGUGGCUCUCCUGGGGGUGCCUUUGGGCAAAAUGCACAUCUGAAUGGCCAGGUGCUUCCCAGCAGUCAGAAAUUAUGGGGGGUGGGGGUGAGAGGGCCCCCUCAUAGCAUCUCACCAAAUCCACAUGGAGGCUUUUUGCAAACAGCAGGCAGUUCCCUUCUGCAGUGACUCCCUCCUAAGGACGCCCCACAACCCAGCUAGUUAAACGUGAGCAUUAAAUUUUUUUUAAAAAAAAUCCCCCUAGUUUCCCAAGACAGCAUUUCCAUGAAUUUAGUCUUCUGUAAAUCACUGGGCAUUUCCGUGAGCCCUUUCUGCCUCCACUCUCUUCUCUGUCUUUGCAGUUUCCUUAUCCCCGACCGCGCCCCCCCUUCCAACCCAAUCACCCCACAAACAAGAUUUCUAGACCCAGUAUAAAAUGAUCCUUUUAGUGACAGUUUCUUGUUAUCUGGCCGAUCCACUGGGGACCGGGCUGCAGCCUUUAAAAUUUUUGAUCCUGGAGGCCGCCGAGCUGAACUUUCCGGCAGGACCCGGGCGAGGGGGGCUUAGCCCUUCGUUUCGAUCUUCCCACCAACAUCCGAGAGCCUAAUCAGCGCGCCCACGGAGGCGCCUUAAGGGCAGUUGGGGAAGAUGAGCAGAGCCGGGAAACAGCAAGAGGUAUAGACCCUCUGCAGCACCUCUCCAAUUCCGCGGCCCUUCCGGGUGGCGUAUACAGCUCCAGGAUUGGGAAAGGGGCUCCGGUGGCCCGGCCCGCGGGCGCCUGGCCUCGAAGCCAGAGGGAGGAGUGCGGGGCGUGGGGUCGGGGGGUGCCGGGCAGAGGAGGAAGCCGUGUCCGGGUCCGCUGGGCGAGGGGUCCUGGGUCAGGGGUCCUGGGUCAGGGCCGGUCUGAGCCCCGGUGCCCCGCAGGUCUCCCCGCGCCCCGGCCGCGCCCACAGGCCCGCCCCCUAGCCGCCGGGGUUGCUAUGCGUUGCCGUGAAACGCCUGUCAAUAAACCCUGUUUGGACAGUGGA